AGGGCGGGGCGCCUCGCGAAGAUGGUGGCGCGCGUGGCGUGUGGCUCCCGUCGUCUGGCCAAGUCUCAGCGCAGCGCACCGGCCGGCGUCUCGUUGGCCUGGAGCCCACACCCACCGGGUCCCUGACCCCGCGCCCCCCGCGCCCGGUUCCCGGCAUGCCUCGCGCCCGUAAGGGCAACACGCUCCGGAAGGGUGGUCAGCGCCGUGGAGGAGGUGCCCGGAGCAGUGCCCAAGCUGACUCGGGUUCCAGUGACGAUGAGGCAGCCAGUGAGGCCCGCAGCACCGCCAGUGAAUGCCCCAGCCUUCUCAGCACCACUGCAGAGGACAGCCUUGGGGGGGAUGUCGUGGAUGAGCAGGGCCAGCAGGAAGACCUUGAGGAAAAGCUGAAGGAGUAUGUGGACUGUCUCACAGACAAGAGUGCCAAGACCCGGCAGGGUGCUCUUGAGAGCCUGCGCCUGGCCCUAGCGUCCCGCCUACUCCCCGACUUCUUGCUGGAGCGCCGCCUCACGCUAGCCGAUGCCCUGGAAAAGUGCCUCAAGAAAGGGAAGGGCGAGGAACAAGCCCUGGCUGCUGCUGUGCUAGGCCUGCUCUGCGUGCAGCUGGGCCCUGGACCUAAGGGUGAGGAGCUGUUUCACAGCCUGCAGCCUCUGCUGGUCUCUGUGCUCAGUGACAGCACAGCUAGCCCUGCUGCCCGGCUCCACUGUGCUUCUGCCCUUGGCCUGGGCUGCUACGUGGCUGCCGCUGACAUCCAGGACCUGGUCUCUUGCCUUGCCUGCUUAGAAAGUGUUUUCAGCCGGUUCUAUGGCUUGGGGGGCAGCUCCACAAGUCCUGUGGUUCCUGCCAGCCUGCACGGCCUGCUCUCUGCUGCCCUGCAGGCCUGGGCAUUGCUGCUCACCAUCUGCCCUAGCACCCAAAUCAGCCACAUCCUUGACAGGCAGCUGCCCCGGCUGCCCCAGCUCUUGUCCAGUGAAAGUGUGAACCUGCGGAUCGCUGCCGGUGAAACCAUUGCACUGCUCUUUGAGCUUGCCCGGGACCUUGAGGAGGAGUUUGUUUACGAGGACAUGGAGGCCCUCUGCAGUGUCCUGCGCACUCUGGCCACUGACAGUAACAAGUACCGUGCCAAGGCUGAUCGUCGGCGCCAGCGCUCUACUUUCCGCGCCGUGCUGCACUCCGUGGAGGGCGGUGAAUGCGAAGAAGAGAUAGUGCGCUUCGGCUUUGAGGUGCUCUACAUGGACAGCUGGGCUCGGCACCGGAUCUACGCUGCCUUCAAGGAAGUGCUGGGUUCGGGCAUGCACCACCACCUCCAGAACAAUGAGCUACUCCGUGACAUCUUUGGCCUGGGCCCUGUGCUGUUGCUGGAUGCCACUGCCCUGAAGGCCUGCAAGGUUCCACGCUUUGAGAAGCACCUGUACAAUGCUGCUGCCUUCAAAGCCCGGACCAAGGCUCGAAGCCGUGUGCGGGACAAGCGGGCAGACAUCCUGUGAAGCAGGACCUGCUGAAGAGGAGACUUUCUAUGCCCUUGGUCCGUAUUUUUAACAGAAGACAGUGCAACAACUGGUCUCCACCAGUAUUUGUCACUUUAUUUUUUUUAAUGACAAAACCAAAAACAGACAUGGGGUGGGUAGCUGGGGGCCCGGACACUUGGGACCCUGACCCCUUUGUCCCUGCACUCAGCCCUGUGGCCCCUUCCUGUCCUGUCUCAGGCCAGGCUAAAUAUGUGCCUUCCUCAGGGCUGUGGGGCAGGCACUAGGGGGCCUUUCCCUUCCUUUCCUUUCUCAGGCCUUGCUCCCCCAGGAUGACCCACUCUUAGGGGGGUGGUGGCAUCUGGACAAAUGCCACCACAGCAGGUGGGGUGGCAAAGCUACCUGGAAUGGAUUUGUGUGCUGAUUUUUAAGGAUUAUUACAGAUAAUUAAACAGAACGGUCAGCCUUCUGUGGUCUUAA